GGGCGCUUCGCUGAUGGUGUCGGUGAGCGCGUUUCCCGCCUGAGCGCAACUAGCGGCGGGUCGUGGGCACCUCCAGAUAAGAAAACAAGCUCAGAGAGAUGUGGUGACUUGCUCAAAUAGUGACAGAACUUCCUCGGCCAUAUGGAGGGGUCAUAUAAUACCCUUGUGUCUUCAGUUUGAGGUACCUCCCAUAAUUUUAAGGGGAGAGCUUGUUUCAUAUCCAUAUCCCACUGUAUUCCUGCUAAUCUGCUAAUGCAGUAAAUUGGAGGAAAACUGUUACCAGGAUAACCUGUAAUGGGCAAGGAGCCACAAAGAAGAAAACAUUUCUUUUAAUUUUUAAACUUGGUUUGAAAGACCAGCAUGUUUUGGAAAUUUGAUCUUCACUCAUCAUCCCACAUAGACACACUUCUAGAAAGAGAAGAUGUAACACUGAAGGAGUUAAUGGAUGAGGAAGAUGUUUUACAGGAAUGUAAAGCUCAGAACCGCAAACUUAUAGAGUUUCUGUUAAAAGCAGAAUGUCUCGAAGAUUUAGUCUCAUUCAUUAUAGAAGAACCACCUCAAGACAUGGAUGAAAAGAUCAGAUACAAGUAUCCAAAUAUAUCUUGUGAGUUGCUCACUUCUGAUGUCUCCCAGAUGAAUGAUAGACUGGGAGAAGAUGAAUCCUUGCUAAUGAAAUUAUAUAGCUUCCUCCUAAACGAUUCCCCUUUGAAUCCACUACUUGCCAGUUUCUUCAGCAAGGUGCUAAGUAUUCUUAUCAGCAGAAAACCAGAACAGAUUGUGGAUUUCUUAAAGAAGAAGCAUGAUUUUGUAGACCUUAUUAUAAAGCACAUAGGAACUUCUGCUAUCAUGGAUUUGUUGCUCAGGCUCCUGACGUGUAUCGAACCUCCACAGCCCAGGCAAGAUGUGCUGAAUUGGUUAAAUGAGGAGAAAAUUAUCCAGAGGCUUGUGGAAAUAGUUCAUCCAUCGCAAGAAGAAGAUCGACAUUCAAAUGCAUCACAAUCACUUUGUGAAAUUGUUCGCCUGAGCAGAGACCAGAUGUUACAAAUUCAGAACAGUACAGAGCCCGACCCCCUGCUUGCCACUCUAGAAAAGCAAGAAAUUAUAGAGCAGCUUCUAUCAAAUAUUUUCCACAAGGAGAAAAAUGAGUCAGCCAUAGUCAGUGCAAUCCAGAUAUUGCUGACUUUACUUGAGACACGACGACCAACAUUUGAAGGCCAUAUAGAGAUCUGCCCACCAGGCAUGAGCCAUUCAGCUUGUUCAGUAAACAAGAGUGUUCUAGAAGCCAUCAGAGGAAGACUUGGAUCUUUUCAUGAACUCCUGCUGGAGCCACCCAAGAAAAGUGUGAUGAAGACCACAUGGGGUGUGCUGGAUCCUCCUGUGGGGAAUACCCGGUUGAAUGUCAUUAGGUUGAUAUCCAGCCUGCUUCAAACCAAUACCAGCAGUAUAAAUGGGGACCUUAUGGAGCUGAAUAGCAUUGGAGUCAUAUUGAACAUGUUCUUCAAGUAUACAUGGAAUAACUUUUUGCAUACACAAGUGGAAAUUUGUAUUGCACUGAUUCUUGCAAGUCCUUUUGAAAACACAGAAAAUGCCACAAUUACCGAUCAAGACUCCACUGGUGAUAAUUUGUUAUUAAAACAUCUUUUCCAAAAAUGUCAAUUAAUAGAACGAAUACUUGAAGCCUGGGAAAUGAAUGAGAAGAAACAGGCUGAGGGAGGAAGACGGCAUGGUUACAUGGGACACCUAACGAGGAUAGCUAACUGUAUCGUGCACAGCACUGACAAGGGCCCCAACAGUGCAUUAGUGCAGCAGCUUAUCAAAGAUCUUCCCGACGAAGUCAGGGAACGAUGGGAGACGUUCUGCACAAGCUCCUUAGGAGAAACUAACAAGAGGAACACGGUAGAUCUACAAGGAUACAUUCAUUUAUACACUGAACACUUUCCUGUCCUAUUGGCUGUGUACCUGAGGACUUGCUCACUUCUUUUGGAUAAGCUGUGCCCAGCCCCAGGCUCCUAUCACUUCUGUAACAUUUUAGUUAAAUUCUCUCUGAGAUACUCGAAGUGCUUUAAUCUUUUGGCUCCAUCAUACCCAAAUACGUGCACAGCAGAUUCAUAUACUCCCUGUGUUUUUAUGUUUGGAGUUUAUGAUGAACAAAAGUUGGUGUUUUAAUUAUAUCCAAAGACCUCUGUGUUUUGACCAAGUCCCCAAACUAAAAAUUGGCAAGGAUUUAGGUAGAGUGAAUUUAGAGAACAUAGGACAUGUUUUUGUACUGACUUUGAAAAAUUUGAGUUUGUUUCAUUUUUUGCCCUCUUCCCCAAGGGGGAAAAUGUAUUUAAAAUUGUUGAUGCUUCUUUCCCAUCAUUGACAAGACAGUGUGUAGAAGAAGAGAUGUAGAAUGAUCUGAAUGUGUGCCUGUAUUAAUCACCAGGAGUUUCCGCAGGUUGGGGUGAAACCUGAAAGUGGGUGUUUCUAACUAAUCCUAGGUUAUGUUGAUGCUGGGGGUCCUCAGUGGGACCAUACUUUGAGGAUCAAGGAAUAAGUCUCUAGCUUUCACUUGUCACUAAUACGGGCCUCAGAGUUUAACAGUCAUUUCACACUUCUGAUUUCCCUUGGGAACCUAAUCAUCCAAAGUAAACACCAAUUUGCUUUUUCCUGUAACAACAGUUAACAAAACGAAAAUUUUAUUUCGAAAGAAGAUAAUAUCUCCGAAACUGUGUGCACUACAACAAGAGUGCACUUUACUUACGGUAUAUCUAGCUUGGCAAGAGUGUUAUAUACUUGUUGCUUUUUGCUGUAUUUGUUUAUAUUCAGUGAUUAUUAGUAUUCAUUAAUUCAGUAAAUAUUUGAGUGCCUACAAUGUGCCAGACACUGAAGAUACAGUACUAGACAAGAUUGGCAAAAAUUUCUGCUUCAGUGGAGAUGGAUAAACAAAUGAGUAAGAGACACGUGUGCACACACAAUAUGUGUAAUAUACAGUCAUGCACUGCAUAAUGUUUCGGUCAGCAAUAGACCGCAUAUAUGACAGUAGUCCCAUAAGAUUAGAAUACUCGAUUUUACUGCACGUUUUUUAUUUGUAGAUACACAAAUACUUAUCACCAUGCUCCAGUUGCCUCAGUAUUCAGUGCAGUACUGUGCUGUGCAGGUGUGUAGCCUAGGAGCAAUUGGUUGUAGCAGAUAGCCCAGGUCUGCAGUAGGCUCUACCAUGUGAACUCUAUGAUGUUCGCAUGAUGACAGAAUUGCCUUUGUCACAAUGUAUCCUUGUCAUGAAACAAUGCAUGACUGCGCGUGUUUCAGAUGGUAAGUGCUAAGGAGCCAACGCAUGGGAGGGAGUUAGGGAGUCUUUGGGGCAGGUGUACAGUUUAAAAUCUGGUGUCAAGGAAAAUCUCACUGGGAAGGUGCAUUUGUGGAGUGGAGAGGGAAGAGCAAAAUGCAGAGGACUCGAAUUUGGGUUGUUCCUAGUGUGUGCAGGGACUUGCAUGUUGUCCCGUGUGGAUGUAACAGUAAGCAAAGGAGAGAACAGAAGGACUUGAGGCCAGAAAGGCGCCAAACAGCCAGAUUUUCUACAGCUUUUUAGUCUAUGGUAAUUUUGAUCUAAUGAGAAUUUGUUAGGUUUUGAACUAAAAAGUGCCAUACCUUGAUGUAUAUUUUUAAAAGAUGGCUGUGGCUAUUGGGUUGAGAACAGACUGCUAGGUGGGGCAAGAGCUAGGAGGAGGGAGACUGGGGAACUGCCAGCUGUGACAUUAGUCCAGGUGAGGGGAGUGCUGGCUUGCACUGGGGAGCUGAUAACAGACUUGGUGAAGGGCGAUGGGUCUGGAGAGGGAUUUUGGCUCCAUUUUGAAGGUAGAGUGGACAUGGUGGGUGGGCUGGAGGAAACAAGAUGACCGAGGUUUCUAGUUGAAGAAGAGUGAAGGUGGCAGUGACUGAGCUGAAGAUGCCUCAAAAGGAGUGUGUUUGGAAGUGUAGAUCAGGAAUUCAGUUUUGUAUACAUCUGAAUAAUGAACCAAUGGGAUUCUGAUUAGCAAGUUUCCCCCAUGGGUAAAUAAUCUUUUUUUUUUUUUUUUUUUUUUUUUUUUUUUUUUUUUUUUUUUGAGACAGAGUCUUGCUCUGUCACCCAGGCUGGAGUGCAGUGGCACGAUCUCGGCUCACUGCAAGCUCCGCCUCCUGGGUUCACACCAUUCUCCUGCCUCAGCCUCCUGAGUAGCUGGGACUACAGGCACCCGCCACCGUGCCCGGCUAAUUUUUUGUAUUUUUAGUAGAGACGGGGUUUCACCAUGUUAGCCAGGAUGGUCUCGAUCUCCUGACCUCGUGAUCCGCCCGCCUCGGCCUCCCAAAGUGCUGGGAUUGCAGGCGUGAGCCACUGCGCCCAGCCUAGGUAGAUCAUCUUUUUAGCUCAUUUUGUUAAUGAUUUCAGACUCAGAUGGUGUAGGUAGAAUCAGACUCACAUCUUCCAUUAAUGUAAUUAUGAAGAUGUGUGUGCAUUGUGUUACUAAUAAGUUGCUAAAACUAGUUUCAUUUUGGAGAAAGCUUUUUUAAAUAUCUUCUAGUAUUGCUUUGAGGAUCCAGUUUAAGUAGAACAUGCGAAGGGGAGGUCACAAUGUCUGGCACAUAGUAGUUCAAUAAAAGUUAGUUUCUUUCUCAUCUUUAAUUAAAGAGUGUUAAAAUCUUAUUUUGUAGGAAAAAGCGAAAGUGUGAAUGAGGAUACAUCGAAUCCUAUUUUAACUUAGACAGCAAGACUUGGCUAAGAGUCGCCAACUCUGUUUUGUCCUAUUUUGCUCAGUUCUUUGCAUGGCCUUCUAUUUCUGUGCCCCACCAUGGGGUUACACCCCUAAAACACACUGGCCCAGCAUGAUAUGUGUGCUGGCUUGCCAGCCAAGUGGCCCGAAGCUCCUCUUGAGUGCACUGCAGUACAACCACUUGACUUGCUCUUUAACAUAGUCCUGUGAGAUGCCAGCUGCCAUGACCAAGCAGUAUUCCCACUCCUCCUCUACACUCUGGCAAGGCUUUCCUGGAACAUCCCCAUGCCCACAUCUUUACCCAGUAACUCACUAAAGCCACUCUUGACUCAAGCAGGUGCCGUUCCUUGAUCACGGAAUCUACCUUUGAUUUCAUCAGGCCAGAUUCACAAACAGAAUGGGAGUGCUUUAUCUAUACCUUUGAGAGGAUGGAGAGUGAAAUAACUGGAAACACUGGGUUAUCACAGCUUAAUUUCAUCCAGGCUUGGUGUCUUUACCAAAGAUGGUUGGGGAAAGGAAGGGAGAUUCAUCUUGUUCAGGCAGUGAUUUGCUCAGAAUUUUACAAGACAUACCCUAUACAGACCUAUUUGAAUUCUACUGUGGGUUUAUUGAACCAGUGUUGGAACAACUUCGCAAAACAGACCAGGCCAGUUAGGUACAGCCUCAUGAGUUGGCAGGUAGCAGCAGCCCGUGUCUUCCCUAAGAUGACAUUCCCUGCCCAAAACACUUCUGUGAAAAGUACAGAAUAAACAGCUCAGAGAAUACAGUGUAAGUUACCCGCAGAAAUAUAGUACUUCUUUCUAGAAGUUUACAAACUGUCCAUGUUUAUCCCUUGCCAUAUAGCAAUCACUACUAUUAGUGCUGUACUUAAUUAUUUGUUUAUCUGAUUUCUAAUUGUUAAUGCUUCCCCCAAAUAUUGUGUGACAUUUGUAAUUAAUAAAAAUCACUUAACGAUGAA